AUCUCUCGGCUUCCGUUGAGCACCAAGCAAGAUGGCAGCUUCCGAGACGGUUAGGCUACGGCUUCAAUUUGAUUACCCGCCGCCAGCUACCCCGCACUGUACGGCCUUCUGGCUUCUGGUCGACUUGAACAGAUGCCGAGUCGUCACAGAUCUCAUUAGUCUCAUCCGCCAGCGCUUCGGCUUCAGUUCUGGGGCCUUCCUAGGCCUCUACCUGGAGGGGGGGCUCUUGCCCCCCGCCGAGAGCGCGCGCCUUGUGAGAGACAACGACUGCCUCAGAGUUAAAUUAGAAGAGAGAGGAGUUGCUGAGAAUUCUGUAGUCAUCAGUAAUGGUGACAUUAAUUUAUCUCUUAGAAAAGCAAAGAAGCGGGCAUUUCAGUUAGAGGAGGGUGAAGAAACUGAACCAGAUUGCAAAUAUUCAAAGAAGCAUUGGAAGAGUCGAGAGAACAAUAACAAUAAUGAGAAGGUCUUGGAUCUGGAACCAAAAGCUGUCACAGAUCAGACUGUCAGCAAAAAAAACAAGAGAAAAAAUAAAGCAACCUGUGGCACAGUGGGUGAUGAUAACGAAGAGGCCAAAAGAAAAUCACCAAAGAAAAAGGAGAAAUGUGAAUAUAAAAAAAAGGCUAAGAAUCCCAAGUCUCCGAAAGUACAGGCAGUGAAAGACUGGGCCAAUCAGAGAUGUAGUUCUCCAAAAGGUUCUGCUAGAAACAGCCUUGUUAAAGCCAAAAGGAAAGGUAGUGUAAGCGUUUGCUCAAAAGAGAGUCCCAGUUCCUCCUCGGAGUCUGAAUCUUGUGAUGAAUCUAUCAGUGAUGGUCCCAGCAAAGUCACUUUGGAGGCCAGAAAUUCCUCAGAGAAAUUACCAACUGAGUUAUCAAAGGAAGAACCCUCUACCAAAAAUACAACUGCAGACAAACUGGCUAUAAAACUUGGCUUUAGCCUUACCCCCAGCAAGGGCAAGACCUCUGGAACAACAUCUUCCAGUUCAGACUCUAGUGCAGAGUCAGACGACCAAUGCUUGAUGUCAUCGAGCACCCCGGAGUGUGCUGCGGGUUUCUUAAAGACAGUAGGCCUUUUUGCAGGAAGAGGUCGUCCAGGCCCAGGGCUGUCAUCACAGACUGCAGGUGCUGCUGGAUGGAGGCGUUCUGGCUCAAAUGGUGGUGGACAGGCUCCUGGUGCUUCUCCCAGUGUGUCUCUCCCUGCUAGUUUAGGAAGAGGAUGGGGUAGAGAAGAGAACCUUUUUUCUUGGAAGGGAGCUAAGGGACGGGGCAUGCGGGGGAGAGGUCGAGGACGAGGGCAUCCUGUUUCCUGUGUUGUAAAUAGAAGCACUGACAACCAGAGGCAACAGCAAUUAAAUGACGUGGUAAAAAAUUCAUCUACUAUUAUCCAGAAUCCAGUAGAGACACCCAAGAAGGACUAUAGUCUGUUACCACUGUUAGCAGCUGCCCCUCAAGUUGGAGAAAAGAUUGCAUUUAAGCUUUUGGAGCUAACAUCCAGUUACUCUCCUGAUGUCUCUGACUACAAGGAAGGAAGAAUAUUAAGCCACAAUCCAGAGACCCAGCAAGUAGAUAUAGAAAUUCUUUCAUCCUUACCUGCCUUGAGAGAACCUGGGAAAUUUGAUUUAGUUUAUCACAAUGAAAAUGGAGCCGAGGUAGUGGAGUACGCUGUGACACAGGAGAGCAAGAUCACUGUAUUUUGGAAAGAGUUGAUUGACCCAAGACUGAUUAUUGAAUCUCCAAGUAACACAUCAAGUACAGAACCUGCCUGAGUAUGACCUCUCCACCUUAUAGUUUAUGAAUGUCUUGUUUGUGAAAGUGACUAUAACCCAAACUUUUUUUUUUUUUUAAAGAGGAUUUGGAAGUUGUAUGGAUUUUUUUGUUAUCUUCACUUUACUGCAUAGGAAACAAUCUACCUCAUCAUUUAAAAUGACAUGGGUGUCGGUUUUGUAGAUCUUUGGUUUUUUUGUCAGGUUUAAUUUCAGUUAACAAAAUGUAAAACAUGACAUUCCCUGCAGAUAUUGUUGUAUACCAGUAUGGUUUCUUCUCUUUCUUUAAAUGUUUUUGGCCAUCAAGUAGCAGUCGUCAGUAGGAGUUUAUAAUACCAAGAAUGUGCUGCGUAUCUUGUCUCAAUAAGUUUUAAGUAACAUUUAAAAAUAUUAAAGCAUGUUAUUUGACCUAAUUUUUUAGCAUUUGAGUUGUUCCAUUAAAUGGAGCAUCUUGUAAAUUUCAAGUAUUUUAUACUUGCAAUUGUUAAGAGUUAACAGGUAGUUGGAUUUGUCGCAGACAAUGAGUUAAGGAAUCCUUUCACGUUUUUCCCAACUUUAAAAUUAAGGAUUCUCAGGUCCCUGUGUAGAGCAGUGAAAAUAAGAUGUGCGUAUGUGUGUGUAUGCCUGGAGAAUUGGUGUUUCACUUCAGUGAGAGGAUUGGCUGUGAGCUUCAGACCAGGAAAUGUGUCAUCUUGCCAGGCACCUGGCUGAGUGUGCUGGAGUGAGGAUCUUGAACAGAAACUUCCUUUUCUGUUAUUAUUCACUACGAAGCUAAAAUGGCCAAAUAUAUACCGUGAAAAUUGGUUUCAUUUAACAAAAGAUCAGAUCCCUCCUUCAGCUGUACACAUUUUUAAAUAAAAUCAUAUUGAACUAAA